AGUCCCCACCCAGCUGACACAGCUCAGGGUGGAGGAAGCCGGUGAGGACAGUGAGACCAAGGGCUUGCUUCGGGGGCUGCCGGCCAAGGCGGCGGCUGGUGGUGGUUUCUGGCUUCGCUGUUCCAUUCCCUUGUCUUGAGGUACCACUACUGGGUUUUGCCUGGGUGCUUGGGACUGGCACAGCUCCCUCGGGGUGGGGAGACUGGGAUAGGAUGCCAAGCUGGUACUCUUGCCUUCCAUCAAUGUGGGGACAGAAGGAGCAGGUUCUCCCGAGAGCAGGUUCAUGGGGCUUCUGGCCAGGGUCAGUCAGAGGUGAAAACUGCCCCCCUGUCCCCCAGGCCCCCCAACCUCUCCCACCAGCCCAGUUUCUACACUCAUGCCUGUUCUGCCAGAGGGGGAGGCCGCACCGUGUCCCUCCAGGUUUUGCCAGGGUUUCUGUCCUGUCUGUUGGGAGGGGGUCAGGAGGCCCAGGUUGCUCAAGCCAGCCCCUCCCCUGCUGGCGUCAUCUGUUUCUCUAGCCUGACCAGGAAAGUCCUCUCCACUCCCACCCCUGCCCCAGGAGAGCCUCUUCCUGUCUCAGGGUGCCCAAGAGGCCCAAGGUGCCACUCCAGAAGGCUUUCCCCUUCUGCCUCUCCUGUGGGCAUGAGGGAGCUGGUGCCUCUUUAGAGAGGAGCCAGAGACAACCUUGUCCCAACCCAGCCUGAUCCAGUUCACCAAGGCAGUUGCUCUAAUCCAGGGGUGGUGGUGGGGACAGGUGGCCAGGGGCUGGUGCCAGACCUUUGGCUGUAAUUAUCGUUGCCUUGUCCCAGGUCUCAGCCGGUUCUCGCUGAGAUGGCUACGUCAGUGAGGCCAGUCACUCCCGGUGCCGCUGCCUUGGCAGAGCUGGUUUAGAACCACCGUGAAGGUCAUCGAACGGGGCCCUCCACCCUGCAAUUGGCCUGCGGCCAUCCUUGAGGCCAUGUGGUCUUUGCAUGAGCACCCAGGAUGGUGAGGAACCUCCGCCUGCUGAGGCAGCCCACCCACUGCAGAAGAGCUGAUACUCCAACCCCAGGCGCCUCACGAGGAAGGGCUGGCAGCAGGCGGCGUGUUUGAGACUGAUAAGCGAGGUGUGUUGGCAGCGCGGGGCCCCAGAGGGCUGCUUGCUCUGCCCUGUUGUUUCGUCAUGGUGGGUUUUAGUCACCCUUGCCCUGUUGGGCAUUAUCUCGUUUGAGGUCCACCUAGAAGGAGGCAUAACUGACACUUGUGGGAGAUUUGCAGGGUCCUGUGCCUGAGCAGCCGGGGGGGAUGCCCCUAUUUGUGGCACUGAGCCUUUGGGUGACUCCCCUUUUUGCCCUGGCUCCAACUGGAAGUAGAAAGUGGUGCUUGAACCCCUGGCAGGCCCUGCUCCUGUAGCCACCCAGGGCGGGAGGAAGCGCUUUCUGCUGCUGGUGUUAGAAACAGUAGGCGCUCUUUCUGCAGCUACAGAAGCUGGCUGUUCAUUCACCCUCCGUCCUGGUUCAGGGACUGUGUUGGAGAGACCCUGUCCACUCGUGUCCUGUGGAUGCAGGACAGGGAUCCCCACCUGCCUGCCUGGGGCGUCUUGUGAGUGACAGCCACUGGGGUCUCCAGGCUCACCGCUGUGCCCCGACCCCGACCUGGCCUGACUCUUCCCUACUGUGCGCCUCCCAACACCGCAGGAGCUUGUCUCCCCAGACACCAGCCCCAGCCGAAGCCCCCAGCCUCUGCUGAGCUGAGAACACUUGGGCUAGUCCUUGGUUUCCACAUUUCCCUGGGUCAUUGUUUUUGUUUCUCACUAGAUGCCAGCUUGUUUGCUUUGAGGAAAACAUAUGGGGGGUGGUGGCUUUAACGCUGGCUUGAGGACAGGGCGGCAGGAGGAGUAGGCAGCCUCGGCUCACGGGCCCUGCCCAGGAGGGCUGCUCUCAGUGUUCCCCAAAGAACCAAACAGCCGGGUCCUGCUUCCUUAGGGGUGGUGUCAUGUCAGCCUGUGCAUCACGGUGGCACAGCAGAGGUCCCGGUUGCCAGCGUGGUCCCUCCCAGCCUCACUUCUGUGACCUUCUGCCCACCUGAGCCUGAGUUGAAAGUCAGUCCUCCAGGUUCCUGGUUUGGUGUUCAAGGCUCAUCACCAGAGGGAGAUCUAGGAGUUUAUGGGGUUCUAGAUGGGCCCAGGGAGGAGGACCCAGGCUGAGCCGUGAGCUGAGAACACCAGCAGUGAGUGGGCCAAGCCCCUGAAAGGACACAGAUGGGCAGAGUCCUGCUGCAUCCUGGGGGCGCCGCAUGCUGGCUGGGCAGACCCUGCGCUGACCUCGACAGGGCUCUGCCCUAAUCCUGGGAAAAAGGGAGGCUCAGCAGGCCGGCAGCCAUUCUCUCCCAAGCUGGACAGCCAAAUCCCUCUUUUAAGCCCCCUGAAUAAAAGAGCUGAAAUGAACUUGCAGAAUAAGCAGGCCCUCGGGGCCCCUCUGCUGCACAGCAGGCGGAGCAGGAGGCGCUCUGAGCAGAGCCCCCAGCCCUCCCCUAGUGCAGGGUCCCAGCAGCAGGGAGAGUGCAGGUGUGUGCAGGAGGCUGGCUGACUUCCCUGCAGGGAAGCGACCCAGCAUGUCCCCGAAGACCUCUCCGUGUUUAUGGUAGACUGUGGCCCUUCACCCUGGGGGCAGGGGACCCUUGCUGCUCCCUCCCUGUCCCCCCUUCUUCUGUGGCCAUUGCCACUCACCUGGGAGCUCAGGUGUUGGGGGCUGAGCAGCAGUGCCCCAGCGCGGAGCCUCCACGUGCUGUCCUCGUACUUCCUUCGUGGGCGCCGCUGCUCCCCUGGGCGCCUCAGCCCAGCUCCUCUGCUGACAGCCAGCUGCUGUCUCUGCCUGGCUUUUUUGUUGUUGGUCGUCCUGGAGAUCCAAGUGUCAAAUUACCGUCGCGAGGGGGAGCCCGAGGAAGCCCUGCUUGGGAACUUGUCCUCCAACUUCAUGUCCCGGUGCCUCACCUCUGCCCUGAGAGCGCUGCUCAGGGACAAGACAAGCUCCCUCUCUCCUCCUCCUUCCUCCUCCUCUCCCUCUCCCCGACUCCCACGCCGUGGGCUGGGCCUGGGUUGGGAGCUGAAGAAAGAAGUCGGCUCUCUGCCUUCCUGGCCAGGAGGACCCUGGGGAGGCUCCACCUGAGCCUGUGGAGGGGAGUCCUGCAGCGCUCUCAGGUCUGGGGCACCCACCCUGCCCUCAGGAAGGCCACCCCUUCUGUCCCUCUGGCCACUCCCUGGCUGGUCCCUCCCUCUGGCCUCUCUCAGGAACAACAGUAAACAGUGGGGAGCUGGUGGCCCUCUCAAGCUGAGCAGGAGGCUUUGCAACCAGUCCCUGGGGAGGCCCUUGUGCCGCUCAGCAUCUGAAGGCGUCUUGGGGGAGAACUUGGAAUCCUGAGUGACCUGGGAGUGGCCUGCGCGCCCGGCAAGGCGCCUCAUGUUCCUUGUGAGGUGCCGCCAUGCCGCCAUUGCCAAGUACUUCGGGGAUGCGCUGCCUGCCUGCGCCAAAGGCUGCGACCACUGCCAGAACCCCACGGCCGUGCGGAGGCGGCUGGAGGCCUUGGAGCGCAGCAGCAGCUGGAGCAAGACCUGCAUCGGGCCCUCCCAGGGGAACGGCUUUGACCCCGAGCUGUAUGAGGGAGGCCGCAAGGGCUACGGGGACUUCAGCAGGUAUGACGAAGGUUCUGGAGGCAGCGGGGAUGAAGGCAGAGAUGAGGCCCACAAGCGGGAGUGGAACCUCUUCUAUCAGAAGCAGAUGCAGCUGCGCAAGGGCAAAGACCCCAAGAUAGAAGAAUUUGUACCCCCAGAUGAGAACUGUCCCCUGAAAGAGGCUUCUAGCAGGAGGAUCCCCAGGCUGACUGUGAAGGCACGGGAGCACUGCCUGCGGCUUCUGGAGGAGGCGCUGAGCAGCAACCGCCAGUCAACACGUACCGCUGAUGAAGCUGACCUCCGGGCCAAGGCCGUGGAGCUGGAACAUGAGACAUUCCGGAACGCCAAGGUGGCCAACCUCUACAAGGCCAGCGUGCUGAAGAAGGUGGCCGAUAUCCACAGAGCCUCCAAGGAUGGGCAGCCCUAUGACAUGGGAGGCAGUGCCAAGAGCUGCAGUGCCCAAGCUGAGCCCCCGGAGCCCAAUGAGUAUGACAUUCCACCAGCCUCCCAUGUGUACUCGCUCAAACCCAAGCGGGUGGGAGCUGGUUUCCCCAAAGGCUCCUGCCCGUUCCAGACGGCCACGGAACUGAUGGAGACAACUCGGAUCAGGGAGCAAGCCCCCCAGCCCGAGCGGGGAGGCGAGCACGAGCCCCCGAGCCGGCCCUGUGGCCUCCUGGAUGAGGAUGGGAGUGAGCCCCUCCCUGGGCCCAGAGGGGAGGUCCCUGGAGGCAGCGCUCACUAUGGGGGGCCCUCCCCUGAGAAGAAGGCAAAAAGUUCCUCUGGGGGCAGCUCCCUUGCCAAGGGCCGGGCUAGCAAGAAACAGCAGCUCCUAGCCACAGCGGCCCACAAGGAUUCUCAGAGCAUCGCCCGCUUCUUCUGCCGAAGGGUGGAAAGCCCAGCUCUGCUGGCAUCAGCCCCAGAGGCAGAAGGUGCCUGCCCCUCCUGUGAGGGGGUUCAGGGACCCCCGAUGGCCCCAGAGAAGUACACAGGGGAGGAAGAUGGAGCCGGGGGACAUUCGCCUGCCCCUCCCCAGACUGAGGAGUGCCUCAGGGAGAGGCCAAGCACCUGCCCGCCCAGAGACCAGGGCACCCCUGAAGUCCAGCCCACCCCUGCAAAGGACACAUGGAAGGGCAAGCGGCCUCGAUCCCAGCAGGAGAACCCAGAGAGCCAGCCUCAGAAGAGGCCACGCCCCUCAGCCAAGCCCUCCGUCGUAGCUGAGGUCAAGGGCAGCGUCUCGGCCAGCGAACAGGGCACCUUGAAUCCCACGGCUCAAGACCCCUUCCAGCUCUCCGCUCCUGGCGUCUCCUUGAAGGAGGCUGCAAAUGUUGUGGUCAAGUGCCUCACCCCUUUCUACAAGGAGGGCAAGUUUGCUUCCAAGGAGUUGUUUAAAGGCUUUGCCCGCCACCUCUCACACUUGCUGACUCAGAAGACCUCUCCUGGAAGGAGCGUGAAAGAAGAGGCCCAGAACCUCAUCAGGCACUUCUUCCAUGGCCGGGCCCGGUGCGAGAGCGAAGCUGACUGGCAUGGCCUGUGUGGCCCCCAGAGAUGACCAACUGCUGGCUGGGCAGGGCCCGCGUCCUCCCCCAGAUUCUAGCAUGGGUCAUCCUGGGCCUCACCUGCUGAUGCCAGGGCCAUCGUCUUUUCUCAGUCCUUCUCCUUUCCAACCAUACUUGGCUUUGGGGAUGACCCCAGACACCCCCUGAAUCCAGGUCAGAGGUCAGCCCACCUUUCUUUCUGCUUGCAAAGCCUAUAGACCCUUCUCAGAGCGGUCCUCAUGGCUGGGUUUUCUGGGACACAUGUCGAGGACAGAAGGUGGAGGGUGGUGGAGCUGCUGCUGGAAGAAGGGGAAGGAAGAGUGGCCCCUCCCCGAGUUCUAAGUCAGGAUGAGGCCCACCUGUCCAAGGUAUCGGAACCUACCCAGGGGACCCUCAGAUCCUCCACCCACUCCCCCAUCCAUUACGAUGCCAGCUUCCAGCCUUGCCCAGGUCAGAGCUGUGGCAGAGGAGAGGCAGCCAGGCCCUGUUCCUGCUCAGCUCCUGCUCAGGAAGGCCAGGCCUGACAGAUGUUUGGGAGAGGAAUAAAGUUGUGUUGUUGUGGGGCAUGCAGGCGUGCACACA